AGUUUCUGAGCGCUCGGCAUCUGAUUCAAUCUCCAGUUUCCUGUUCUUGCUGGGGCUGGGGUCUCUCCUUUAACAAAGACACGCCGCGCGGCCGAGUCCAGGGGCUGCAGAGGCCUGGCGCGCGCACGCGCACGCGCACGCCCACCGCGCGGCUUCCCGCGGUCCCCGGUGCUGAGGAGAGAGCGAUCCGAGGGACUGCGCCGCCCGGACGGCCUGCAGAGCGCUGCCAUCAUGAGUGAAAUUCGUAAGGACACCUUGAAGGCCAUUCUGUUGGAGUUAGAAUGUCAUUUUACAUGGAAUUUACUUAAGGAAGACAUUGAUCUGUUUGAGGUAGAAGAUACAAUUGGGCAACAGCUUGAAUUUCUUACCACAAAAUCUAGACUUGCUCUUUAUAACCUAUUGGCCUAUGUGAAACACCUAAAAGGCCAAAAUAAAGACGCCCUUGAGUGCUUGGAACAAGCAGAAGAAAUAAUCCAGCAAGAACACUCAGACAAAGAAGAAGUACGAAGCCUGGUCACUUGGGGAAACUAUGCCUGGGUGUAUUAUCACAUGGACCAGCUUGAAGAAGCUCAGAAGUAUACAGGUAAGAUAGGGAAUGUCUGUAAGAAAUUGUCCAGUCCUUCUAACUACAAGUUGGAGUGUCCUGAGACUGACUGUGAGAAAGGCUGGGCACUCUUGAAAUUUGGAGGAAAGUAUUAUCAAAAGGCUAAAGCGGCUUUUGAGAAGGCUCUGGAAGUGGAGCCUGACAAUCCAGAAUUUAACAUCGGCUAUGCUAUCACAGUGUAUCGGCUGGAUGAUUCUGAUAGAGAAGGGUCUGUAAAGAGCUUUUCUCUGGGGCCUUUGAGAAAGGCUGUUACCCUGAACCCAGAUAACAGCUAUAUUAAGGUUUUUCUGGCACUGAAGCUUCAAGAUGUACAUGCAGAAGCUGAAGGGGAAAAGUAUAUUGAAGAAAUCCUGGACCAAAUAUCAUCCCAGCCUUACGUCCUUCGUUAUGCAGCCAAGUUCUAUAGGAGAAAAAAUUCCUGGAACAAAGCUCUCGAACUUUUAAAAAAGGCCUUGGAGGUGACACCAACUUCUUCUUUCCUGCAUCACCAGAUGGGACUUUGCUACAGGGCACAAAUGAUCCAAAUCAAGAAGGCCACACACAACAGACCUAAAGGAAAGGAUAAACUAAAGGUUGAUGAGCUGAUUUCAUCUGCUAUAUUUCAUUUCAAAGCAGCCAUGGAACGAGACUCUAUGUUUGCAUUUGCCUACACAGACCUGGCCAACAUGUACGCUGAAGGAGGCCAGUAUAGCAAUGCUGAGGACAUUUUCCGGAAAGCUCUUCGUCUGGAGAACAUAACCGAUGAUCACAAACAUCAGAUCCAUUACCACUAUGGCCGCUUUCAGGAAUUUCACCGUAAAUCAGAAAAUACUGCCAUCCAUCAUUAUUUAGAAGCCUUAAAGGUCAAAGACAGAUCACCCCUUCGCACCAAACUGACAAGUGCUCUGAAGAAAUUGUCUACCAAGAGACUUUGUCACAAUGCUUUAGAUGUGCAGAGUUUAAGUGCCCUAGGGUUUGUUUACAAGCUGGAAGGAGAAAAGAGGCAAGCUGCUGAGUACUAUGAGAAGGCACAAAAGAUAGAUCCAGAAAAUGCAGAAUUCCUGACUGCUCUCUGUGAGCUCCGACUUUCCAUUUAAAUACAUACUCUAGGAAAUUAGCUCUAAGUUUUUCCCUUCAUUUUGGGUUCUCCUGUUUGUUUUUUUUUUAUUAUUUUAAUCCCUUGUUUAUUAUAGAGCUAAUAUUUAUUGAAUAGUUAUUGUGUACCAAGCAUUGUGCUAAAUACUUUAUAUGCAUUAUGAUGAAUCUUGUGCGGUUUUCUUUCUUUUUUUCUUUUUAAUUAAAAUACUAUAAUCCAUUGAGAAAUAGCAAUAUUCUAGCUAUUGUAACUUCUAAAAAUGGUAUGGCCAUUAGAUCUGUGCUUUUUAUCUCUGCUCUUUGAAUUUCUCAUAUUAUAUAGUAAAUAUAUUCCUACGUAAACCUUUGAUACCUAGAUCAGGAAUACUCUUCCAGGAGUACAAAAUUACAUUAUUGAUAGUUAAGCUCUUAAUUGUGUAGCUUGCAAAAGACAGCACUUUUUAGUUACAGAUGUUUUGACUUUGAUGAGGAUAUUUAGCUAUCAAUCUAAUAGUCACCUAAAAUAUCUUUUUUGUUGGAAAAAAGUUUAUAAUAAAAAAGUUUGUCAUCUCUAGUGACUUCAAUAAAGAAAAAACUAGAAGAGGAGAAAAAGGAUUUCCUCAAAUUUUAAAUAUGUAACUUCAGGGAUUCAAUCCCCAAAUGUUUAUUAAGUAGCUAGAAAUAAUUAUGUGGAAAAAAAUGAAUAAUGGAAAAUAGUGAGUCUCAAAUUGUUCUCUUUUUUUUUUUAACUAAAACAAAUCUGCAAUGAAUCUAGAUGCAAUUAAUUUUAUUCCUUCCAACUAAAAUUACAAUAUUUUUAGGUUAAAAUUAUUGAGAUAUAAAGCAGCCAUUGGGAAAUUGGGAGAAAUGAUAAACAAAUGGAAAAAGAAGAUGUCCCUAACCUACACCCAUAGAUUACCAAGGUUUCAGUGUACUAGUUUUGAAUCUGUUCUGAAUGGAGUUUUUAUACCCUCAAUUUCUGGCCUUUGGCUAUUUUAGCAUUUCAAAGUGACUUCUAUGAAGCUUUUUUUUUAAUGUGAAAUUUUCAGAAUGUUGUUUUUUUCAUGUAGAUACUCCAGGAAGAGUUAAGCACUGCUUUCAGUUUUAAUAUCCACCUUGAGGGGUCGCUGCUUGAGGGCUCUUAUCCCAGGGGACUUUUUAAUUCGGAUGUUACUUAAUGUGGCUUCUCUAAUGUAGUUUCUUUGAUUACCGACUACACAAUUAUGUACCAUCACAGUAUUAGUGGAAAAGUACCAUGUGAUUUAAUUCUCCAUUCCUCCAAUGUAACUCUUAAAAUUAUUAUGUAUGUGUGUGUGUUUUACUUUUUGUUUUUUAUCAUCUUUAAAAUUUCUAUUAUGGUUUGAUUAUUAUAAAAAUAAUGAAUUCUCACUGUAAAUUUCAAAAAAAAAUUACAAAAGUAUGUGAAUUUAAAAAUGAGAGCAGUCCUCUCACCCUACCACAGUUCCACACCCUCAAGGUAAACUUAUAACUUAUAAUUUGAUAUGUAAACUUCCAGAUCUUUUUUCUAUGCGUAAUCAGACAUACAUAUAUACUGCAGUGUAUCUCACGUAUUAAUUUUUAAAAAUCUUUUGUUUUACUUAAUUCUGUUUUUAUUAUUAUUAUUAUUUUGUUUGAUCUAUUAAGGAAGAACAAGGAAGGGAAUGAUCUUUACUCAAGAAUUUCAGAAAGUCAGCACUGAAGUCCUGACCUAUCAGUAGACACAUUUGUCCCUUUCAGAUAUUUUAGGAUAUUCUAGCAAAGCAGGCCAUUUCUCCCACCUGAAAGUACAUAACUUCUAUCACUUGCCACAUAAUUAAAAGAACUCACAUUAAGCGGUUACUCAGACAGUUAAUCAUAGAAAAGAUUAUUUGCUUCAUCAGUUCAUAGAAAAGAUUAUUUGCUUCAUCAGUUAACUUGUUUUUAUAAAUCAGGGCUGUGUUCAUACACAGAAGGGGCCUGAGAUUUCUGCACUUUAAACAAGCUCCUCCUAGGUGAGGAUGCUGUGGCUGUUCUAAUUACAUUUUGAGUAGUAAGGUCUACAGCAUUGUUCCUCAAACUUGGCUACGUAUUGGAAUCACCUAAAAAGUUAAAACAAAACAUGGAUGUCUGGGUCCCGCCCCAUAGAGAAUGACUUAAUUGGCAUGGGGUGCAGUCCAGGCAUCAUGAUUUUUAGAUUUCCCAGUUGGAACUUGUGCAGCAAAGUUUGGGAGCUACUGAUGGACAUGUGAAAAGUAAGUAUAAAUGGAAUAAAAUUAAUUAGGCUAAUAGGCUUAACCCAGGAAAUCCUAAGUUCCUUGAAUAUCCAGUUUGCAUUUGGACUCCUCAUCAUAUACUUGGUAUAUAAUACUCUAAUAAAAGCUGCCUGAGUUGAA